GCCAUUUAAAAGAUUCGCCUAGCUUAGAGUUGGAACGAAAACUCUUUUUUGCACUUUUAAAAGUCCACCCAGGUAGACGUGUUUGGGAAGUUUUUUCGGGUGGGAAAUGGGCUUCGCCCGUACGAACAAUCCGGGGAAAUCGCCUCAAGGAGGAUCCUUACGCAGCAUGUGGAAAAAAGUUGAGGGCAGGGGUCUGUGGCCACAUUUUCCAUCAAAAAGUCCCUGUUAGAGGCAGUCUAAGAAAGAGAGAGAAAGAGCGAAAAAGAAACUUUCCUAUCAAAAUGUUUCAAUUAAGAAGUAGGGUGUACGUGUGAGGGGAAGAGGACGCUGGGCUCCAACGUUUCAGUAGAAGCGCUUAAGACUUGCAAACACCCUUGGUGGGGACCUGGAACCCCGGGAGAUGCCGACGAGCAAGCAGGUUGGCUGCCCGGCGGGUCUCUGUGAGAGAUCCAGGUAGAUGGUGAACGGCCCCGGCAGCUGAGGGCAGGCCAGGCCCCCAGACGCAUCAGACCCUGAAGGACUGCGUGGUGGGAGCCCUGCACCGCUCCUGGCCCCGGGCCCCCUGGAUCCGUCGGGGCGCCUCCACCCAGCUGUUAGCAUGAUGUCUUACCUCAAACAACCCCCAUACGGCAUGAACGGGCUGGGCCUGGCCGGGCCCGCCAUGGACCUCCUGCACCCAUCCGUGGGCUAUCCGGCCACUCCGCGGAAGCAGCGGCGGGAGCGCACCACCUUCACGCGUUCACAGCUGGACGUGCUCGAGGCGCUCUUCGCCAAGACUCGCUACCCUGACAUCUUCAUGCGGGAGGAGGUGGCGCUCAAGAUCAACCUGCCGGAGUCUAGAGUCCAGGUCUGGUUCAAGAACCGCCGCGCCAAAUGCCGCCAGCAGCAGCAGAGCGGGAGCGGAACCAAGAGCCGCCCAGCCAAGAAGAAGUCCUCUCCAGUGCGGGAGAGCUCGGGCUCCGAAAGCAGUGGCCAAUUCACGCCGCCAGCUGUGUCCAGCUCUGCCUCGUCCUCUAGCUCGGCGUCCAGCUCUUCCGCCAACCCAGCGGCUGCAGCGGCUGCGGGACUAGGUGGGAACCCGGUGGCGGCCGCGUCGUCGCUGAGUACACCAGCUGCCUCAUCUAUCUGGAGCCCGGCCUCCAUCUCGCCAGGCUCAGCGCCCGCGUCCGUGUCGGUGCCGGAGCCAUUGGCCGCGCCUAGCAACACCUCGUGUAUGCAGCGCUCCGUAGCUGCAGGCGCCGCCACCGCAGCAGCCUCUUAUCCCAUGUCCUACGGCCAGGGCGGCAGCUACGGCCAAGGCUACCCUACGCCCUCCUCUUCCUACUUUGGCGGCGUGGACUGCAGCUCAUACCUAGCGCCCAUGCACUCACAUCACCACCCGCACCAGCUCAGCCCCAUGGCACCCUCCUCCAUGGCGGGCCACCAUCAUCACCACCCACAUGCGCACCACCCGUUGAGCCAGUCCUCAGGCCACCACCACCACCAUCACCACCACCACCACCAAGGCUACGGUGGCUCUGGGCUUGCCUUCAACUCUGCCGACUGCUUGGAUUACAAGGAGCCUGGCGCCGCUGCUGCUUCCUCCGCCUGGAAACUCAACUUCAACUCCCCCGACUGUCUGGACUAUAAGGACCAAGCCUCAUGGCGGUUCCAGGUCUUGUGAGCCCAGGAAUGAAAGAGGAGAAGAAACGCAACUACCUGCGCCCUCCGUGGUCCCGAUCCUGUUGCUGCUGCUGCACCGCCCGCCUUUGCCUCGUCUUCUCCAAAACUGAAUUUUCACCCCCCAAAAAGAUGUCCAUUGCCUGCACUGCCGCCCCCAUUUUUGUGCCACUUGCUUGGGGGGAUGUGCAAACCCACCCUGCCCCUUGGAUGGGGGGACCGGUGCUUCGGCUUGGCCUACACAUUCUAUACAGGAGAGAUGUAUUAUUUCCCCCCUUCAGCCCCUACUAAACUCUUAAGCCUCCCCUUCCAGUCUUUCUGGACAGCUAUUAAGCACUUGCAGCCUUCGGAGGCUCUGCGCUCUGAUCCGCUGUUUGAGCCCAACACUUUAAUUUAUUCUUUCUGGACACUGGAGUCACUAACUGGCGUGUUUCUGCCCAUUGGAGCACCCGCACACUACUCCAAAUCAAAACCACUAAGAGUUCCUCCCGCGCAGACUGCUGCCCCUUCAGCUGCCCUCGAUUUUGCUCCACGCCUGCCGGCCAGAGCCUCCCGGCGUUUCUUCCGCCCCAGCGGAGUGCGCUGGGGCGCGCCAGGGCUAGGCCCGCCGGAGGAGCGCGUCCCCAGCCUUCCGCGCACAGAGCCGCAUCCCGCCCCGCCCUGCGCUGGACUGGUUCAAGCUUCCGCCUCGGCGGGAACGCUGUACAUAGUCAGGUCCGUUCCAGGGACCACUUAAACUUUUUAGUUGCUGUUGGUUGGUUGAACUGAACAUAUCUUGUCUUAGCACCCAGGAAACAGAACUUUAAGAUAUAUACAGCACAUAUAUAUAUAUAUACAUAUAUAUAUACACAUAUAUAAAAAACAAAAGCAAAAAAUAUUUUCCCUCUGUCCGUCCCCCUUCUGCUCUUCCUCAAUCAAUGGCGCUUUUUCUUUUUCAGUUGUUGCAAAGCUGCCCUGCCCUCUUCACAUCUUCUCCCUCUGUGUAUUUAUUGAAGAGAACCGCUUGGUUUCAGGAAGCUGGGCGCGGGAUAUCCGAAGUGUGGAGGAAACAGACAAGUCAGGGUACAGAGGUGGGGGUUGGGCAGGGGCGCAGGGCUGACCCCCUCACCCGGUCUAAGCACAGGGUCGCAGUUCCAGUUUACAAACCUAAAACAAGAAAACCAAAACCAGGGAACAAAACAACAAAACAAAACAAAAUCCGUAAAAGUACAGCAUUAGGGAAAAACAAACAAACCCAGGCCCCAAACCCAGUUCCAACUCCUCUGUCGGCUUCUCUCUUUCAACACCCUUGUUUUGUCUAGUGAGUUUUUAGUGCACCUUCGUUCUCCGAAAUCUGCGGAGAGCCCGCGCGCCUGUGUAUCAAUUUUGGCUUUGGCCGCUUCGUCCAGUAGGUGGGAAAGUAAUUUGUAAAUUUGAUUUGUCUGAUGUGAAGAUCACAAAUUACUUGUUGAAAUGUAAGGCAGUCCCCCUCCUCCUCUUUAUCUACAUUACUUCCCGAAAAUAAAUGCAAAUUAAUGAA